GAGCUCGGCUGGGCUUGGCGAGGCUGCGGCGCGGCCACCGGCGGGAGUGCAGCGGCCACUGUACCCAGAGAUUCAAAACCCCAAACCCGGGACUUGGGGGCGCUGAGCCGGGCCGGGAAGCAGAGCCUGGUCGUGAGGAACAGCCGCCCGUUGCUGUCUGCCCCUUUGCGGACAGCGUCUCCCUCGACUCCGCUUAGGAAGUGGUGGGGGCGGCGUGGCCCCCGUCGGGAGGCGUUCGAACGCCCGCUAGGAGAGAGAAAGGAUUCCCCUGUGCUUGGAGCCCGCACUCGGGCGCGGAGGGAGCGGCGGCAGGCUCUCGCUUUCGGCACCAUGGGCUGCACGCUGAGCGCCGAGGACAAGGCGGCGGUGGAGCGGAGUAAGAUGAUCGACCGCAACCUCCGUGAGGACGGCGAGAAGGCGGCGCGCGAGGUCAAGCUGCUGCUGCUCGGUGCUGGUGAAUCUGGUAAAAGUACAAUUGUGAAGCAGAUGAAAAUUAUCCAUGAAGCUGGUUAUUCAGAAGAGGAGUGUAAACAAUACAAAGCAGUGGUCUACAGUAACACCAUCCAGUCAAUUAUUGCUAUCAUUAGGGCUAUGGGGAGGUUGAAGAUAGACUUUGGUGACUCAGCCCGGGCGGAUGAUGCACGCCAACUCUUUGUGCUAGCUGGAGCUGCUGAAGAAGGCUUUAUGACUGCAGAACUUGCUGGAGUUAUAAAGAGAUUGUGGAAAGAUAGUGGUGUACAAGCCUGUUUCAACAGAUCCCGAGAGUACCAGCUUAAUGAUUCUGCAGCAUACUAUUUGAAUGACUUGGACAGAAUAGCUCAACCAAAUUACAUCCCGACUCAACAAGAUGUUCUCAGAACUAGAGUGAAAACUACAGGAAUUGUUGAAACCCAUUUUACUUUCAAAGAUCUUCAUUUUAAAAUGUUUGAUGUGGGAGGUCAGAGAUCUGAGCGGAAGAAGUGGAUUCAUUGCUUCGAAGGAGUGACGGCGAUCAUCUUCUGUGUAGCACUGAGUGACUACGACCUGGUUCUAGCUGAAGAUGAAGAAAUGAACCGAAUGCAUGAAAGCAUGAAAUUGUUUGACAGCAUAUGUAACAACAAGUGGUUUACAGAUACAUCCAUUAUACUUUUUCUAAACAAGAAGGAUCUCUUUGAAGAAAAAAUCAAAAAGAGCCCUCUCACUAUAUGCUAUCCAGAAUAUGCAGGAUCAAACACAUAUGAAGAGGCAGCUGCAUAUAUUCAAUGUCAGUUUGAAGACCUCAAUAAAAGAAAGGACACAAAGGAAAUAUACACCCACUUCACAUGUGCCACAGAUACUAAGAAUGUGCAGUUUGUUUUUGAUGCUGUAACAGAUGUCAUCAUAAAAAAUAAUCUAAAAGAUUGUGGUCUCUUUUAAGUUUUGCAGUUCAUGGUAAAAUGCAUUUUCAAACCAAAUGAGUACUUAUAUAUGGAUCUCUGUAGACUAGAGUCUUGCAGCAACACAGAAUGUAAUAUAAGGCAAAUGCAUCUGGGACUUGACCAAAGUUGUUCUGUUUUGUUUUUUUAACUGAAAGUAACAGAAGGACCUUUCUUAAAUGUGACAGAUGGUCCUGCAGUGUGAAACUGAAGGACAGUGUUAAAGCUGGGCUCUAGUAUAUUGAUGAUUUCUGCAUAAGUGUAAAUAUGCAAAUGUAUGUAUACAUGUAUUUAUGACUUUAGUUUUCGACAUUAUUUUUAGGUUUUAAGAGUGGCAACUUAGGAUUUUAGGGUGAUGGCUUUGGAAAUAACAUAAAUAUACCUUGUACUGAAUGACAGACUAUUACUACGUUUGCCAGUUUUAAACAGCUUUAUUUAUGUUCAUGUCCUGUAAAUUUUUAAGUACAGUAAUUAAUAUUAGGAAACAUUACAGCCCUUAUCUAGAUUAUAUGUAUACUUGUAUUAAUAAAAAUGUUAUUUGUACAAACAUUGCACAGACUAUUUUAAUAACAUGAUUUGUUCUUUAAAUUUUAUGUGUUUUAUUGAAAUGUUCUUAAGAUGAAUACACCUGCCUUUGGAUCAACUAUUUAAACAUUGUAUGCAUUUUGAUUUUUCCUACUUUAAGAAAAUAAAAUAAUUUAAUUUUACAUUAGAUUCCACGUUAGAUUUGGUUUGAAAAACUAAAAUUUCAGAUUUCUGAGGAUAUACUGUCUUAGACUUAUUGUACACACUUAGUUUUUAUUCACUUGUUUUCACUCUGAAUUUUAAUAUUUGGCUGAUAUGAAUGCAUUGCCUCAAAGGUGAUGUCAUCUUAAUUUUUAUUCACUUUAAAUAACUACAUUUUUGUUUAUAACUAAGUUUGGAGGGAUCCUAAGAGCAUUUUUGUGGGUAAAAAAAAAACCUGUGGACAUAAUGAAUUUUGAGACAUUGAUUGGUGAGGCUUUUAUUUCCCUUGAGGAGUCUCUUGUACCUAGCAUACAUGAUAGCUCCUUGUUGGGAAGAUAACAAGAAGGAUCUUUGAAUACUCUAUUGCUGAUAUAAUGCAAGAUUUAAAUUUAUACAUAUAACUAAUUUCAAAUGUAAUUAUCACACUAUGUUAAAAUUACUUUUUUCCCUUAGAUAAUUCAAAUUUCUCCACUUGCUUGAGAUUAUAUCAUUUCUUUUUCAAUUAUACUAUUAUUUCUGAGAAUGAAAUGGACGAUUACACUUAGAAAAUGAGUAAUAGUGUUUAAUAAGUCAGUGAUUAUAUGUGUGCUCAAAUAAGUGUUAUGUAUCAGCUAGAUACUGAGCUUUGAUAGAAUAAUUUUCUUUUGAUUAUUCAUGAUGUGUCAUCUCUGACCUUGUUUCAGCAAAGUAAACAGCACUCCCCACCCCACCCUCCUUUUUUUACUCAUCUUGGAAAAGGUUAGUCUUUCAGUACACGUUGCUGGUAAGUAGUUUCCAAGUUACGUGUUGUCACUGGGUUGAAGUAUAUUUGUGUGUGUGUGUGUGUGUGUGUGUGUGUGUGUAACCAUAAACUAUAUUCAUAUCUGUUUCAUUUGGAGGAUUUUCUUCUUUGUAAUGUAAAGAAAUUCAAAGUUAUCAAAGUUCCUUAAAUGUGUUAGUUUAGAUUCUUUAUGUGCCUUUCAUGAAAGAUAUGUUUUCAUUAAUUUUACUGGUGGACCUGUAAUAUCCACAUUGUGAAGCUGUGUAUGAAAUUCAACUAUAAUAUGAAUAAAUUUGAAUCAUGAGAAUUAUGGGUUAAAAAGCCACAAAGAAGCACAUAUUGGUGACCAUCAUUAAUGAAAUCCUGAACUUUAUUCUGUGUAAUUGUGUUAAUAAAUCCUAAUAAAUUUAAAUUUUUAAAAUUUUACAAACCUAUUGGCUAAGUACAUUUUGGAUUAGAAUUUAAGUAUCAGUCUGUUGUUUCUUCAUUUCUUCUUUUUCUAUGCUCUUUUUACAAUUUCAGCUACUCCAGAAGCUCAGAUUUUCCCUGUUCCAAGCUAUGAGAUGUGAUGCCACAUUUGGAAUUGCCUUCUUGAUAUCCCCUUCUGAGAAUGCAUUGCCUGCUUUUUAACUCAUUAUAUUCAAAACUAAAUUCAUCAUCAUUCUCUCCUUACACCAGUUCUCACCCUGACUUUGCCAUUUUUCCUUACUAAGUACCAUCAUCAUUUAUUCCUUCAAUGGGGAACUUUUUAGUUUAAGUUCUGGGAUACGUGUGCUGAACAUGCAGGUUGGUUACAUAUGUAUACAUGUGCCAUGGUGGUUUGCUGCACCUAUCAACCUGUCAUCUAAGUUUUAAGCCCUGCAUGCAUUAGGUGGAACUCUUCUGAUUCCUAAUCUCCAUUUCAAUUUACUGACAGUUCUACAAAGCCUUAAAUCUGUUUUUUGUUUGUUUUCCUUUCUAUUCCUACUACUACCUAUUCAAGUCUUUGCUAAACUUCCUCUUAAAAUGGCAUUAUUAGUUAAAUUCCCCACCUCCCAUUUCUCUCUUCUCGAAAAACCCAGGUUAGUUAUCCUAAUGUAGAACUGUGGCCCUAUCACCUUCUAUUCCUUGAUCUGCAUUGGCUCUGAUUUGUCAAUAAAAUUAAGUAUAAGUUAGCCUGCCAUUUAAUGCUCUUCAUCACCUGAGGCCUGUUCCUUUCUACACUGUAUCCAAAUAGUGUCCUGUGCAUAACCUGGGCUUUCCUCCAAGUACUGUAUUACUUACUACAUGUGAUAUGCUUAGAGCAGUGCCUACAAUGUGGGAAGUGUUCAUUUGUGUCUGUCAAUGUUAUUUUUAUUAGCACUUUUAAAAUGGUGUGUAAAAUGUAUUGGCACUUUUAAAUUUGGCACUUUUAAAUUUGUUUGUGAUACCUCUUUUAGACUCCUCUGGCAUCUGUUCUUCAGGGUGCCCUUCUGGGAACUACAUGAUUCUGAUAGAGCUGCCAAUCGCAUUUCUUACUUCUCCGUCUCUAGGCUUAGACCUGACCAAUCCGAGUCCUCCAGCAUUGGACGAGUGAGCCAAUCAUUGUCCCAGUUGCCAUUCUUAAAGUCCCUAAGGCGCUUGUGGUUUCUAAAAUUCUCUUCAUUUCAGUAACCUUCUAAAAGUCUACUUUUUUAUGCCUAAUCUAGUUUAAUCGAAUUCAGUUUGUUACUGAAAAAGUACUGAUUAAAAUCCAUAUGUUCUCAUUGAAUACUGACAGUAACUAGAGAUCAAAAAAGGCUUAAAGAGGUUAAUUAACUUGAGCAAGACCAGAUGAAGGUUUUAAACCUAGAGCUUCUGACUCCAUGUCUGUCAGAGGACCCCAAAGAUGCUACCUUAUUUCCAGAAAAUGUGUAAGUAGUGUUUCGCCUAUCCCCACUCUGCCCUUGAGUUCCUCUGAGCCAUAAUAGUUUUUCAGAUUUAAAAAAGGAGAUACUUAUUAAUGUCUUUCAUCAGAGCUAUUUUUUACUCCUUAGAUGUGAAGCUACUUAAGAGCACAGUUACCAUUUUUUACAUCAUUUGCCGUUUGCAGAACCACCUUAUGUAAAUGAAUUUAGUUGAUACUGUAAUCAUUAUUACAGAUGGUAGCAUCAUCAUUGCUUAGUGUGUUAUGUUGGAAGUAGAAAGUGAUGGUGAAAAUCCUAGGCUCUGGCACCCCGUCUGGCUUCAAAUCCUGGCUCAAUUUCUUAUUAACUGGGAAAAUCUGGGCAAAUAAUUUAGUUUUGCUCUGCCUCCAUUUAUAUCAUCUGAAAAUAAAUAAGGAUUAAAUAAUCCAUUAAUUUUAAUGGUUGUUGUCAGCAUUAAAUAAGUUCACAGUACAUGUUAAGUACCUAGAGGGGAGUGUGGAAUGUAUAAGCCGUCAAUACAAUUUGCUGUUAUUUGAUUAUAAAUAAUAGUUUUAAGGUGCCUUUAAAAUCAUAAUCAGUGCUUAACAAAUGGUUGUUGAUACGUGCUUUGAAUGAAAUGCCUCAAAAACAAAACUCUCAUAAUUCGUUUUCAUAAUGAAAACUAAGUGUCUCACAUAUUGAUACUGGAAAAUGAGAAAAUGCAAUCUCUAAUCAACUUGAGGACACUUCUGUCGUUUUAAUGUAACCAAUAGUAUGAGAGAGUUUAUAUUUUAAUGUUAGGUUGGAAAUUUUCUUUUUUUUUUUUUUUUUUUUUUUUUGGUAUGGAGUCUUGCUCCUUCACCAGGCUGGAGUGCAGUCGUGCAAUCUCCACUCUCUGCAACCUCCAACUCCAUGGUUCAAGCAAUUGUCCUGCCUCAGCCUCCCGAGUAGCUGGGAUUACAGGCAUGCGCCACUACACCCAGCUAAUUUUUGUAUUUUUAGUAAAGGGGGGUUUCACCAUGUUGGCCAGGAUGGUCUUGAUCACCUGACCUUGUGAUCUGACCGCCUCGGCCUCCCAAAGUGCUGGGAUUACAGACGUGAGCCACUGCGCCCAGCCAGUUUUCUUUUUUAGUUCUUUUCAAAACCCUUUCUUAACAGUUGAAAUGCAUUUAUAUAAAGAAGUUUACGUUUCACAAUCCCACUGGCCUGUUUCCCAGGCAUUUUUUUAAACCAAUUACUGUUUGCUUUGGUGUCUGUUGUGAUUUCUCUUAUUUAGUUGGAUUUUGUAGUUACUUUAAAAGUUACGAAAUUUCACAUUUCAUCAAGUCCAGAGGCCAGAGACACCCAAAUAUGCACAGACAGGAAUCAGCUGCAAUUGUCCAAGCCAGAGCUGAUUAGGCCUCAACUGGAAUAGUCCCACCAUGUAAUAAAUCUUCCUGAGUAUUGUGUAUAAGGUCAAAUAUUUCCAGCUUCUUUGAUUUUACUGCCCGUCUUCCUAGGUCUCCAUCCGUAAAGUGGAUGGAAACACUGUCAUUGAAGGAGCUAGUUCUUCAAAUUUAAUUUUUUUUUUUUUUUUUUUCCUGAGACAGAGUUUCGUUCUUGUUUCCCAGGCUGGAGCGCAAUGGUGCGAUCUCGGCUCACCGCAACAUCCGCCUCCCGGGUACAAGCAAUUCUCCUGCCUCAGGUUCCCGAGUAGCUGGGAUUACAGGCAUGCGACACUACACCCAACUAAUCUUGUAUUUUUAGUAGAGACGGGGUUUCUCCAUGUCGGUCGGGCUGGUCUCGAACUCCUGACCUCAGGUAAUCCGCCCACCUCGGCCGCCCAAAGUGCUGGGAUUACAGGUGUGAGCCACCGCACCUGGCCAAAAUAUUUUUAAUUGAUUAAAAAUGAGAUAAUUUGAGGAAACAUGCAUAGAAUACUAGACAGAGACUAUUUUAGCAGAUAAGAGUGCCACUUUUAGUAAAAGAAGUUGUCACCUAGAAGAAAGUACAGGUGCUCCUUGACUUACCGUGGGUUAAGUCCUGAAAAGCCCACUGUAAGUUGAUAAUACCUUAUUUUGAAAAUGCAUUUAAUACACCUAACCUACCAAAUGUAGCUUAGCCUGGCCUAACUUAAAGGUGCUCAGAACACUUAGAUUAGCAUACAGUUGGACAAGAUAGCAUAAAGCCUAUUUUACAAUAAAGGAUAUCUCAUGUAAUUUUCUUGGAUACUGUACUGAAAAUGAAAAACAGAUUGAUUGCAUGGGUACUUGAAAUAUGGUUUCUAACUGAAUGCAUACCAGUUUCGCACCAAUGUAAAGUUGAAAAAUUGUUAAGUUGGACCAUCAUACGUUGGGGACCAUCUGUACAUAGAGUAGGACUCUUGAGAGCCUAAGGGCCACAGAAAUUCCUUUUCCAACUGCAGUGUCUAUGGAGGGAUUCUUAUAAUUAAUUUUAUUCCUGUGCAAACACACUAUCUGUGUAUUCUCUAUUUUACCAGGAUUUUUUGUUUUUGCUAAAUUAGACAUACAAUUUUGCAGUUAUUUUUUACUAAGUUGACAAAUGUUUGUACAAUUUCAGUGUAAAGCUAGUCUUCAAAAUAAACCACUGUGAAGAUUGGAUAUUACCUUGGAUUUUCUGUUGUGCACUCUUGAAUUUUAAUUAUGUUCUGUGGAAACUUCACAGAGUUUUAGCUUUGAUCCUUCCUUCACUUUUGAAAAUCAAGAGUAAAGUUAAGUCAAAGCUACUUCUAAACAGCUCUAUCUUUAAUUUCUAUUAAAUAGUACUGAGGUAUCAAUUUUGUAGCUUGUGGAAUGCGGACUAUCCCAGCAGCAAAUUCAUUAAUAUGGUUUGUAUAGGACUCACUUUGCAGCAUUCAAUUUUAGUAUAACAUGUUUUCCUGUUUACAAAUAUAAGUAAUUACCUUUCCGUUUUAAGUGACCAAUUGUCCUAGCAAUCUACUUCACAAGGCAAUUUACCUGUAAUAAAUAUAACUUUUUUGCAGACUUGAGCAUACGUUUAAACCAUUUAACCAUUCUUGAAUUUCUUAACAUAGUAAGUUACAAAUUUUAACUAUGAAUCUUCUUCUUCGAAAGGAAUCUUGUCUAAAUCUAAUAAAGCAUUUUUCUGGCUGAAGCUGCAAUGGAAAGCUUCAGUAUGAAGCUGGCAUAAGGAAAGCCAGUAAAAAGUGCCCUUUCUUCUUUCUGAGAGCCCCACCUCUGAUCCUCCUACACUUAAGGCUUCUAGAUGCAGAUUUAUACAAUAGUGCUAAAUCAAGACCUUGAAAAAUGUACUCAUAUAGUAAGAUUUACUCAAAACCACGAACUCCUCCAUUAUUUAAAAUAUGUUAGAGAUACAUAAAUAUAUAGAGAAAAUGCAUACAUACAUAAUUUAUUGAGUGCCUACUGUGUGCUAGGUACUUUUCUGGGUACCUUACUAAUGCUCUCAUUUAGUCAUCAGAGCAGUCCUGCAAUAUUGGUAAAAUUUCCAUUUUCUAUAUAAGGAAACACAUUUAAGAGAGGUUAGUAUUUUGUGCAAUGUUGGCUAUCUAGGAAGUGGCAGAGCUGGGUGUAAAAUCUAGAGUUAAGACCUUUGUUAGCCAUAUCUUCAAAAUCCAGUGUCAUUUCUUAGCCAUAUCUUCAAAAUCCAGUGUCAUUUCUUAGCCAUAUCUUCAAAAUCCAGUGUCAUUUCUUAGCCAUAUCUUCAAAAUCCAAUGGCAUAAAGAAGUUUUUCACAAGGGUGCCACAUGGUGUAGUGCAGCAUGUCCAACAGCAUUGCCUGAACAGAUGUUAAUAAGUAUGCAUGAUGCACAUUAGCAUGUCAAUGGCUGUGAAAAGCCAGUGCAGUAAAGAAGUAAAGAGCUCUCUGUGUGUUAACCCUCCAUUUCACAAACAUAGGAACUGCACAGACACAGCAGCCACUACCCAGGUGUGAAUGCAGAGCACUUAAAACGUAGCUAGUCCAAAGUGAGUUGGCCUAUUAGUGUAAAAUACAAGAGUUCAGAUACACAGAAUUUAAAAAUUACAUGUUGAACUGAUUUGUGAUAUAUUGGGUUAUAUAAUUUUAAAAUUCUACUUUUUUUUACAUUUUUAAUGUGGUUUUGGAAAAUAGGUACUCAUGUGUCUUUGCAUUAUAUUUGUAUUUGGGAAAUGAAAUGCUUUAUUUUUCUUCCACAACAACUCUAUUUGCAUUGCAUGGAAAUGUUCCCAAGUUUUAGAGAAACACAUACAAAAACUAAAAAGGAUAGAAUGCUAAAAUUUGAAUGUGGAAGAUGUGGGUCUUGGUGUCUUGAAUAAAUCACACCUUCAGUGACUUUCUUGGGAAAUGGUGGGCCUCAGUAAAGACUUGGACUAUUCCAGUUUUAAAUGCUAUCGUUUGGUUUGGUGUAAUAUAGCCUUUCCUGUGGGGGGAAAACCCAUCUCAUUUUCACUUUAAAUAUGUCAGCUAUAAUAAAAGAGAGACAUACACAUUUUAAGAUCUAUACUCUAAAACAGGGUUUUGAAAUUAGCAGCUCUCUUUAUUUUUAGUUCCAAUACAUGGAGGGGGAGUUGACCCUUCAAGAUACUGGAAAAUUAUUAAAUCCAGUUUACAGACUCAUCUCUUUAGUCUGCAGCCAAAUCAAAAGAUUAGUGGGGUUUUUUUUAAUGUUGUUAUUGUGUUGUGUUUUGUUUUUUUAAUAUGUUUCAAUUCCCCUAGCCAAAUUCCUUUCUUUCUCCACACCUCCCACAGGACUGGGCUGAGCACAGUCAUGCAUUAAAAAAGCUUCUGAACUUAUUUUGGAAAGAGUAGCUCCCUGGAGUGUGGAGGAGGACAGGAAUUUGCUAUCUGCAGGACUUAAAUCAGGAUAGAGUAUCAAAUAUUCCAAGGCCUUACAUGCAUGUUUUGUUUUUUGAUAAAGACAGAAGAUUGCAAAUGGUUUGCUCUUUAACAGUCAAUAAAAUCAUAUCUACUAAUCAAUACAUUUGAAGUUUACUAGAUUCUCAAACUUUCCAUAAGAUUUGAGUUCAUUAGUUUAAUGGGAUCGAUCUGAGAAAAAUUAGAUUUAUGUGCAGAUUUUAGCUACCCUUGUCCUUGGAAUGUGUAUGCACACACACACACAUCUGUGAGAAUGAUUAUUUUCUACUUGAUACAGUGUGCAUCAAAUAAAAGUUUACUAUAUUGGAAUAUGGGAAUAAAUUCAUUUAUAAUUAGUUGAAAUUGUCCAGACACAUAUUUUAGAAAAGUAUGUUAUUUUUGUUUUAAGUUUGGAAGAACCUGAAUGAUUAAACCUGAUUUAAGUCCCUCUAACAAUUAUGAAGAAAAAAAAAGACUAGAUUUUAUAUCAACUUAAUUGUCUUUUGGUUUAAAAUUAUGUAUCCAAUAAAGACAUUUAAAAAGUAAA